AGACGCACUUCCCGCCUUCGCCUAGGUCUGCACCGCCACCGCCGCCCUCUCCCGCGCGUCCCUCACCCGGUCCGCCACUGCCGCGCCUCAGAAUCCGAAGGCUCGGUUCCAGCGCAGCCAUCCACGCCGCCGCCACGACCGACUCCGGAGCCACGCGCUGCAACCGCCACCAACGCCUUGCCGCCGCCGCUCGCCCGCCGCCCACCAUGGCCCAGCAGCAAACAGGUAGCAGGAAACGGAAAGCGCCCGCGGUCGAGGCGGACGCCGAGAGCUCGCCGUCGCAGGGCUUGGCGGCAGCGGACGGUGAGGGGCCGCUGCUACUCAAGAGGCAGAGGCGGCCGGCGACGUAUCGCUCGAUGGCGCACUAUCUGAAGGUUCGGGAGGUAGGCGGGUGGGGCCCCGCCAGGCUCCAGGGCUUCGAUGGCGAGCUGCGGGGCUACGCGGUACAGAGGCUGCCCGAGCUGCUGACGGAGCGCCAACUGGAGCUGGGCACGGUCAACAAGGUGUUCGCGUCACAGUGGCUGAACUCCAGGCAGGUGGUGUGCGGCACCAAGUGUAACACGCUUUUCGUGGUGGACGUGGAGUCAGGCCACAUCGCGCGCAUUCCCCUCUUGCGGGACAGUGAGGCCAGGCUGGCCCAGGACCAACAGGGCUGCGGCAUCCAUGCCAUCGAGCUGAAUCCCUCCAAGACGCUUCUGGCCACCGGCGGCGAAAACCCCAACAGCCUGGCCAUCUACCAGCUGCCCUCCCUGGAUCCCCUGUGCCUGGGCGACCGCCAUGGCCACAAGGACUGGAUCUUCGCCGUCGCCUGGCUGAGUGACACCGUAGCCGUGAGCGGCUCCCGCGACGGCACUGUGGCGCUGUGGCGGAUGGACCCGGACAAGUUCGAUGACACUGUUGCCUGGCAUAGCGAGGUGGGUCUCCCCGUAUAUGCCCACAUCCGUCCGAGGGAUGUGGAGGCCAUCCCCAGGGCCAUCAUCAACCCCAGUAACCGCAAGGUGCGGGCCCUGGCCUGCGGCGGCAAGAACCAGGAACUGGGAGCGGUGUCCUUGGACGGCUACUUCCACCUGUGGAAAGCCGGGAGCGCACUAUCCAGGCUGCUGUCCAUCAGGCUGCCCUACUUCCGGGAUAAUGUGUGCCUGACCUACUGUGAUGAUAUGUCUGUGUACGCCGUGGGCUCCCAUUCCCACGUCUCUUUCCUGGAUCUGCGCCAGGACCAGCAGAACAUCCGGCCCCUGUGUUCUCGAGAGGGUGGCACAGGCGUGCGGUCGCUGAGCUUCUACCGCCACAUCAUCACUGUGGGCACCGGUCAGGGCUCCCUGCUCUUCUAUGACGUCCGGGCCCAGAAAUUCCUGGAGGAAAGAGCCUCCGCCACCCUGGAGUCCUCUUCGGGACCUGCAAGGAGGAAGCUCAGGCUUGCCUGUGGCAGAGGCUGGCUCAACCACAAUGAUUUCUGGGUGAAUUACUUUGGUGGCAUGGAAGUGUUUCCCAAUGCGCUCUACACCCACUGCUACAACUGGCCUGAGAUGAAGCUCUUUGUGGCUGGGGGGCCUCUCCCUGCAGGCCUCCAUGGGAACUAUGCAGGCCUCUGGAGCUAAGGAUGACCGCCUUGUACUCCAGGUGGAACCAGCCCAGCUUAAUUUGUACUCCUCCAAGCAGAGAGAGUGAGUGGUCCUUUGGUCAAUGAAAACUUGGCUUUAAGACUUUUUGACUCCUUUCCAACACCAUCUUUUGGAAUUUUCAUACAAAGAAAUUUGGUUAAUCGUUAAUCUUUAGUUGCAUUCUCUCUUUGAGUGAUUCAUACAUUCUGUUUCUUUAAGAAGAUGCAGUCAUGGUCUUUCAGUUAUGUAUAUUUGUUUUCCUUGUUUUUCCUCGUUACCAAUAUUACAACAGCAUUGUUUUCAGUUAUUUUUCAUUGCAGAUACGAAGAGAAAAUUUUCUAGUAAGCAAGGUGUUCCUACAUCUUUUCUGGAGAGCUUACCAUAGUUUUAUAGCAUUGUUCAAUUGGAAAAGUACAUUCCAAGUUCUAGAUUACCUACGUUUGGAAACACUUAAUUUACAAAUUGUGAUCUUAGUGUAUAUAGUUUUUACGUUGUUGGUGCUAAAGUGCUUUUUUGAAGUUUAUUCUCUUUCAAAAUAAGUUAUCAUAGAAUCUUGUGCUUGUAUCAAACUCCUAAUUGGUCGGAACACUUUAGGAGUGCAGGGGUUCUGCUUCAUUGCAUUUUCAGAAUUAACCUGAAAGUUGAAACAACCAUUUUUUUUUAUUUCAAAACUUAUUUAAGUUGUUAUCACCUGUCCUUAAAUAGAUAAAAGAAUGUGUAUUUUUUCACUUGUUGCCUUAGUACUAUCAAGACUUGUGAAUAUAUUUGAAUGUAUGUUGUUUGAAAAACUUGCACAGGGCAUUGGAGCCAUCAUGAAAAGCAGGAAAUGUAAACGUGGAAUGUAUGGCAGGCUGGGCAGAAUGUAUACUGAUCCAGGGUAUAGACUAGAUAUUUUUGCUGUUGCUGUUUUUAUUAUAAAAUGUUAUAUUUGAGGAUAUUUAACAUUUUCCAAUUCUGCUUAAGAGGUAAUUCACAAUAAAAAAAACAAAGACCAAAAAUAGCACAUUCUGAAAAAAAGAUUCUUAAUAAGAUUUUAUUUUGUGAAGUUCAAAGAUUCUUUCCUAAAGUAUAACGUGUUGUUAAAAAGUAGUGGUGUUAUAACUCUCAAUGUAAUAGUAUGCAAUAUCAAGAACACAGGAAGUUCGUUUCAAGAUAGGUGAGAUUUAAAAUAAAUAGGAUGAGGUUGAAGAAAAGUAUAUUGGAGCGCAGAUAAAUAUAAAUUGUGGACUGCUAUGAAAACAGGUUGUACUUCUCCAUAUGUGAGACUACUGGAAGUGAGAAGCAAUAUUUGUCAUUUCUAAAACUGGCCAGGCUGUGCUGACCCAGGAUUAGUAAUUUGUUAUGUCUGUUUUCCCUUAGAUGUUUGGGCACUCAGAUGCUAUCUUGGUGCACACACACAACAUUGCUGUUCAGUCACAAAUCCGAACAACUUAAUAUAAUAAAUUGUACUAAAAGUCAUUUAAGAAAUACCAAAAAGUAAGCUUUUGUUUCUAACCAUUGUUAUAAAGGCUAAUAUAAUUGUUGUUAUAUAGCAGUAAGAUAUAUUUGUGUGCAUGCGUCUCCAAGUCAGUUGUAAAUGUCUUGAGAACAGAGAAUACAAUUGUCAUCUUUAUAUUGCCUCAUUUCUCCACUAAUACUUAGCAAAUAAAAGGCAAUAAGUAAAUAUGUACUGGUUGAAUGCCUCUGGAGACCUAGAGUUUAAAGUUUUAAGUCAAUAAAUAAAUAAAUAUUUACUCUUAAAUAA